GAGCCGGCCCAGCUGCUCGGAGGCUCUGGCAUGGUAACAUCCCCGCGCGGGGGUGGAGGGGCUCGGGGCGGUCCCACAGCGCCCCCUGCGGCCCGGGCCGUGGCCGAUGGGGCGGGGAGGCCGCUGGGGAUAGCUGGGACCCCGGGGAGGGCGAGGGAGGCCAAGGGUGAGGGAAGAGAGCCCGGGAGGGGGGAUGGGGGCGGGGACUGGGGGCGAAGGGGCGGGGGAGGCCAUGAUGGAGCCUGGCCGGGGGCGAAAGGUGCGAGAGUGGCGGGACUGGGUGAAGAGUGGGAUUGGGAGAGGUGGGGGUGGGUUCGCGGAGAAAGAUCGGGAAAGAAGAGAGAGGGCGGAGAUGAGGGGACUGAGGGGACCAGGGGACAGGUGGGGACCAGUUUCCCCUCCUGGGAUAUUUGGUGUGCGACAUGCCCUUCCCCCAGCCCCAGCGCCCGUUCCCUUUGGAAGCCUGGGUGCUCCUCAGACCACUUGGGGACUCCCUGCUUCACCUUCCUGCAUUUGCAAGAGCUUGUCUCCUGAGGUGGAGAGGGGGCCUCUGAAGAAAGGGGCUCCCAGCCCAGGCCAUCAACAAACUAACGACUCUGUGUGACCUUGGAUGCCCCCUCCAGGGAUCCCCCCACCCUUUCCUCCGAUGGGGCUACCCCCCAUGAGUCAGAGACCACCAGCUAUCCCCCCCAUGCCACCUGGCAUCCUGCCCCCAAUGCUUCCACCAAUGGGGGCGCCACCACCACUCACACAGAUACCAGGAAUGGUACCUCCGAUGAUGCCAGGAAUGCUGAUGCCAGCGGUGCCUGUCACCGCAGCGACGGCUCCGGGUGCGGACACCGCCAGCUCUGCUGUGGCUGGGACAGGCCCUCCGAGGGCCCUAUGGAGUGAGCAUGUGGCCCCAGAUGGGCGCAUCUACUACUACAAUGCUGACGACAAGCAGUCCGUGUGGGAGAAGCCCAGCGUGCUCAAGUCCAAGGCAGAGCUGCUCCUGUCCCAAUGUCCCUGGAAAGAGUACAAGUCGGACACAGGCAAACCUUAUUACUAUAACAACCAGAGUAAAGAGUCCCGCUGGACCCGGCCCAAGGAUCUGGAUGACCUAGAGGUUCUAGUCAAACAAGAGGCUGCAGGGAAACAGCAGCAGCAGCUGCCACAGACACUUCAGCCACAGCCACCUCAGCCACAGCCUGACCCCCCACCUGUGCCUCCUGGCCCCACCCCAGUGCCCACAGGCCUCCUGGAACCUGAGCCAGGUGGGAGUGAAGAUUGUGAUGUGUUGGAGGCCACCCAGCCCCUGGAACAGGGGUUCCUGCAGCAGCUGGAGGAGGGCCCCAGCAGUUCUGGACAGCAUCAGCCACAGCAGGAGGAGGAGGAAUCAAAGCCAGAACCAGAGAGGUCUGGCCUCAGUUGGAGCAACCGGGAGAAGGCAAAGCAGGCAUUCAAGGAACUGCUGAGGGACAAGGCUGUCCCCUCCAAUGCCUCAUGGGAACAGGCCAUGAAGAUGGUGGUCACCGACCCCCGUUACAGUGCCUUGCCUAAACUGAGUGAGAAAAAGCAGGCAUUCAAUGCCUACAAGGCGCAGCGGGAGAAGGAGGAGAAGGAGGAGGCCCGGCUAAGGGCCAAAGAGGCCAAGCAGACCCUGCAGCAUUUCCUGGAGCAGCAUGAACGCAUGACCUCCACCACCCGCUACCGGCGGGCAGAACAGACCUUUGGGGAGCUGGAGGUCUGGGCUGUGGUCCCUGAGAGGGAUCGAAAAGAGGUUUAUGAUGAUGUCCUCUUCUUCCUGGCCAAGAAGGAGAAGGAACAGGCCAAGCAGCUCCGGCGCCGCAAUAUCCAGGCCCUAAAGAGCAUCCUGGAUGGGAUGAGUAGUGUCAACUUCCAAACCACGUGGUCCCAGGCCCAGCAGUACCUCAUGGAUAACCCCAGCUUUGCUCAGGACCAUCAGCUGCAGAACAUGGACAAGGAAGAUGCACUGAUCUGUUUUGAGGAGCACAUCCGAGCUUUGGAGAGGGAAGAGGAGGAGGAACGGGAGCGGGCCCGGCUUCGGGAGCGACGCCAACAACGCAAGAAUCGGGAGGCCUUCCAGACCUUCCUGGACGAGCUGCAUGAGACAGGGCAGCUGCACUCUAUGUCCACCUGGAUGGAGCUAUAUCCAGCAGUCAGCACUGAUGUCCGCUUUGCCAACAUGCUGGGCCAGCCGGGCUCCACCCCUCUGGACUUAUUCAAGUUCUAUGUGGAGGAGUUGAAGGCACGAUUCCAUGAUGAAAAGAAGAUCAUUAAGGACAUCCUUAAGGUGAACACGGCCUUUGAGGACUUCGCCCACGUCAUAAGCUUUGACAAGAGGGCUGCCGCACUGGACGCAGGCAACAUCAAGCUGACCUUCAAUAGUCUGCUGGAGAAAGCAGAGGCACGGGAGAGGGAGCGGGAGAAGGAGGAGGCACGCAGGAUGCGGCGCAGGGAAGCUGCCUUUCGAAGCAUGCUGAGGCAGGCUGUGCCUGCUCUGGAGCUAGGCACUGCCUGGGAAGAGGUCCGUGAGCGUUUUGUGUGUGACUCAGCCUUUGAGCAGAUCACCCUGGAGUCGGAGCGGAUCCGGCUCUUCCGGGAGUUCCUACAGGUGCUGGAGCAGACUGAAUGCCAGCACCUCCACACCAAAGGCCGAAAGCAUGGCAGGAAAGGCAAGAAGCACCAUCACAAGCGUUCCCACUCACCCUCAGGCUCUGAGUCAGAAGAAGAGGAGCUGCCCCCACCAUCUCUCCGGCCCCCCAAGCGGAGGAGGCGGAACCCCUCAGAGUCAGGCUCUGAGCCCUCUUCCUCACUUGAUUCAGUUGAAAGUGGGGGUGCUGCCCUUGGAGGACGGGGCUCCCCUUCCUCCCAUCUUCUUGGAGCAGAUCAUGGCCUUCGGAAAGCCAAGAAACCAAAAAAGAAAACUAAGAAGAGAAGACACAAGUCGAAUAGUCCUGAGAGUGAGACAGACCCUGAGGAGAAAGCUGGCAAGGAGAGCGAUGAGAAAGAACAAGAACAGGACAAGGACAGGGAGCUCCAACAGGCAGAGCUCCCUAACCGUUCCCCAGGCUUUGGAAUCAAGAAGGAGAAGACAGGCUGGGACACGUCAGAAAGUGAGCUGAGUGAGGGUGAGCUGGAGAGGCGGCGGCGGACACUCCUACAGCAGCUGGAUGAUCACCAGUGACCCAAUGAGCUGUUCUCUGCCUCGGGUCUGUGUGAGGCCAUGGCUCCUGGGCCACCCUCACCGUCUGCCUCAGACUUCUUCCUUAGUCUGGUCUGUGUCCACUUUUUCUAAAGUAACCCCACCCCCAGCACACCAUUGUUGGCACCUCUCAAGGUUGCUCUUGGUGUUCAAGGGUCCCCUACUCCCUGGACUAGUGCAGUCCUUGCCCUCAGCCCCAGACCAGAGAUGGGUGGUAUAUGCCAUGUGGGGUGGGUGAUGCCAGUAGAUAAAAGUGUGAGAGAAGGGGUCUCCAGGGAAGAGUCACAGGCUGUUGGACGCAGCCUGGGUGGCAGAGGGCAGGGUCAUCACCCUCUAGCAUCAGUGCCUGCUCCUGCCUGCCCUGGCCCUGAGGCUCCACCACUUCUUCCUCCACCCAGGACCUAAUGUACGUGUGUUUUGUUUUUUGUUUUUUAAAUAACAAUAUUUAUAACAUG